GUGGCUCCUGGAAGCAGGGCUGGCGUAGGGCCGCCAUGUUGCAGCAGGAUAGUAAUGAUGACACUGAAGAUGUUUCACUGUUUGAUGCGGAAGAGGAGACGACUAAUAGACCAAGAAAAGCCAAAAUCAGACAUCCAGUAGCAUCGUUUUUCCACUUAUUCUUUCGAGUCAGUGCAAUCAUCGUCUGUCUUCUCUGUGAGUUGCUCAGCAGCAGCUUUAUUACCUGUAUGGUUACAAUUAUCUUGUUGUUGUCGUGUGACUUUUGGGCAGUGAAGAAUGUCACAGGUAGACUAAUGGUUGGCCUACGUUGGUGGAAUCACAUUGAUGAAGAUGGAAAGAGCCAUUGGGUGUUUGAAUCUAGAAAGGAGUCCUCUCAAGAGAAUAAAACUGUGUCAGAGGCUGAAUCAAGAAUCUUUUGGUUGGGACUUAUUGCCUGUUCAGUACUGUGGGUGAUAUUUGCCUUUAGUGCACUCUUCUCCUUCACAGUAAAGUGGCUGGCGGUGGUUAUUAUGGGUGUGGUGCUACAAGGUGCCAACCUGUAUGGUUACAUCAGGUGUAAGGUGCGCAGCAGAAAGCAUUUAACCAGCAUGGCUACUUCAUAUUUUGGAAAGCAGUUUUUAAGACAAGUAAGUGUUUUCUGGAUGUGAUCAGUGACUAAUGCAAUUAUUUCUAACUUUCAUAGUUUAAUUUUUAUGAAACGCUCCUGAACAGAAGUUUUAAAGGCAUAUAGUUGUAUAAAUAUAAUGAUAAAGAUGUUGUAAUUGCUCUUUGGGGGUGUUCAAGACAGUCUGGAAGUGUAUUGUCAGUAUCCUAAAAUUAUUUUAAAGCCAGGAAGGAUAAACUAUCAUUGAUAAUAACUUAUUUUUUAAAAAUUACUUUUAAGUUCAGUUGUUUUUCAUCAAUUAUGGGAGCUUUAAGUGAAUGCCCUUGCAGAAUGUAUGUUGUAUGUUUUUAUUUUUAUUUUUUGAGACAGAGUUUUGCUCUGUCGCCCAGGCUGGAGUGCAGUGGUGCAAUCUCGGCUCACUGCAACCUCUGCCCCCCGGGUUCAUGUGAUUCUCCUGCCUCAGCCUUAUGAGUAGCUGGGAUUACAGGCGCAUGCCACCACGCCCAGCUAAUUUUUUGUAUUUUCAGUAGAGAUGGGAUUUCAUCAUGUUAGCCAGGAUGGUCUCCAUCUCAUGACCUUGUGAUCUGCCCACCUCAGCCUCCCAAAGUGCUGGGAUUACAGGCGUGAGCCACCGUGCCCAGCCUGUAUGUUGUAUGGUUUUAGGGAGAACAGUUGAAUCACAAGAAGACCAUAACAUUUGUACUCAGAUGUUUUUUUCCCCCUAGAACAUAAGGAUUUUACUAUAAUACCUCAACAUCAGGGUUUUCAGCAGGAUGAGUAGUAGUCAUAGGUAAAUAAUUAUUGGUUAAAUCUCUUGGGAAAAGUGACUAGGUCUUUUUUUUUUUUUUUCUUGAGAUGGAGUCUUGCUCUGUCGCCCAGGCUGGAGUGCAGUGGCGUGAUCUCGGCUUACUGCAAGCUCCGCCUCCCGGGUUCACGCCAUUCUCCUGCAUCAGCCUCCCGAGUAGCUGGGACUACAGGCGCCGCCACCACGCCUGGCUUUUUUGUAUUUUUAGUAGAGACGGGGUUUCACCGUGUUAGCCAGGAUGGUCUCGAUCUCCUGACCUCGUGAUCCGCCUGCCUCCGCCUCCCAAAGUGCUGGGAUUACAGGCGUGAGCCACGGCGCCUGGCCGUGACUAGGUCUUUAUAUGAGUAAUACCUUGCAUUUGGUUAGUACAGUAGGUUGGGCAAGUGAUAUUAUGUAGGACAGGGAUUCUUAAACUCGAACAUACAUGAGAAUCACCUAGAGGGCACAAGAUUGCUGGGUUCCACCUCCAGACUCCUUAUUCAGUAGAUCUGGGGGUGGAGUCUCAUAAUUUGCAUUUCUCCCAAGUUUCUGGGUGGUACUGAGGGCACUGGUCCAGGGAUUACAUUUUAGAUAACUAAAGCCCCGAGAAAUUAAAUUAUUUACUUAAGAUUAUACAGCUAAUAGUGGUACAAAGCUAGAUCUUAAACCCAGCCCUCUGUACUCAAAAUUUAUUGUUCUUUUUAUUCUACUGUACAGUUUCUCUCACAGAAGAUGAAAAGUAGAGAAAAUGAAUAUUCAUGUAGGGACAUGAUCAUCUCAUUCUGAAGGAUUUUUGCAUGGCUCCAAUAUACCUUUACUGUGGUCCACCUUAGGGUAACUUUCAUGUAUGUGCUUAUUAGGUUUUUUUCGUUAGAAUUUUCAGUGUUUCUGAAGGUGGGGAGGAACAUGGAAUACAGGUGAAAUUAAACCUUAAACCUGGCAUAACAUGGAUAGGGUUAGUGUCUUACAUGGUAUCCGGCGUCUGCUCAAAUGAGACAAACUGGACAGCUGGGUGGAUGAUGGUAUCCAUGGAUUUACUUCAUUAGCGCAUGUCUACUUUUUUAUUUAUUUAUUUUUUUUGAGACAGAGUCUCACUCUGUUUGCCCAGGCUGGAGUGCAGUGGCGCGAUCUCGGCUCACUGCAAACUCCACCUCCCGGGUUCAUACUAUUCUUCUGCCUCAGCCUCCCGAGUAGCUGGGAUUGCAGGCGCCCGCCACCACGCCUGGCUAAUUUUUUGUAUUUUUAGUAGAGACGGGGUUUCACUGUGUUAGCCAGGAGGGUCUCGAUCUCCUGACCUCAUGAUCCACCCUCCUCGGCCUCCCAAAGUGCUGGGAUUACAGGUGUAAGCCACGGCGCCCAGCCUAGCAUGUCUACUUUUUAAUGUGAUUGGGCCAUUGUAUGUAAGGUAAUGCUCUGCUUAGAAAUAUAGAAUGUUUUCCUAGGCCUAGGCCCCAAGUCCAUGGUGUGUGAAGUGAAAUAACUUUGAUGUUAAGGAGUUCUUUUUUUGUCUUUUGCGGAACACUGGAGAUGAUCAGACUUCCUGAAUAGAGAAAGCUUAUGUGCUUUGUUACAUUGGGGAACAACUGAAGAGAUUCUUGACUCAACCUUUUAGAGCUUAGUCCAUGUUGCAACGAGGAGUGUUGGCUUUGUUUUUCCACUUAAAAACUUUAUUUAUAAAAAGGAAAAGUAGUUUUCAUAUUAAGUUUUUAUUUCCUUUCCAGCAGUUGGGGCUAGAAAGUAUAUGUUGGCACUAGAAACAUUGUUAAGAUUUGUUCUGUGGUGUAGGUAUGCACAUUCCAUAGGUAUGCACACGGCCAUGUAAUACCUGUAUAUCCCAAGUUAAUGAAAGUGUUCAUUUACACAGAUAAUGGAGACCUUUGCAUUUUGAUCCAUAGAACAUAGGAGGAUGUUCUUAGUCUGUCUCAAAGCUCUAUAUGUUUACAUAUUAUUUCUGUAGAUUGUUUUCAGGAGAAAGUUUUGCUUCUAUGGUAAGAGUGAGCACUUUGGCUUAUGUAUAAGUUAGAAAUAAUUGUUAGUUUUUAAUAUGUACUUCAUGGGGAAAUUUCUUAGACGUAUGCAAGCAAGUGAAAACAAUUAGGGCCAGUGGUAUUAACUACUUUAUAAAAUUUUAUUUUUGUUUGUAAGAAGUUAUCUACUUAAGGCCCAGUUAAUAUAAGUGGAAUCAUCAUAGUUUAAGGAAUACCCAGAGAUUGCUGCUAUUCUAUUUAUUUUACAGAAAGGAUAGCUAGAUUGAAAGUUCUUCAGUGGACCUUGAGCUAAUAGAUCUUUUACCACUAAAAGAGCAUUAUUCUCAUGUCAUAAUGAGAAUAAUAAUUUACAUACUUGGCAUAAUAAAUGCCUAAAAGACAUUUUAUUUUCUGAAUCUAUUUUUUUCUUGCUAUAAUGGGGAUAUUGUAAAUUAUGCAUUUGUAUUAAUGGUAUUUCUUAAAGCAAUCUAUGUAACUGUAAAUUAAACCAAUCUACAAACUAUUGUAGGCAUCUGUAAAUUCUGUUGUAGGUAUUAUAAACUUUGUUGAAGUCUUAAUCAGCAGAUUAUGUUGUGAAUAUAUUUGUACAUUGUUAAAAUAGUUUUUAAGAUUAUUUGUUUAAUUGAAUAAGUGUCUUAUUGGAGUGAUAGCUUUGAAGGUGCAAAACUUUAUAUUUGUAUAAAAUUCUACUAUUUACAAGGCA